AGAGUCCCCAGGUGGCACUGUCAGAGUCGCUCAGUGGGAACCUGCGCCAGCCGGCAGGAGACGUGGCUGUCCUCAGCCUGGCAGUGCGUCUGGAGGGCCUGUGCGAGCUCAGCCCAGGUGUGACAGCGGGGUGGUAAGAGCAGCAGCACCCUCAGGGCAUCCGAUGGGCGGAGGCCCCUCGAGGUGACACCCACCACUCAGCCGAGCGGGACUACGAGUCUGCUUUGUGCUCCGCGAGGACCAGAAACACCUGCAAGAGGCACGGAGAGGAGGCGCCUUUCAAGAGGCGCCUUUCAUGGAACUGAGGACUGGCCUGGCUUGGGGACACCAACAAGCCUUCCCCCUCCUGCUGGACACAGAGACACCCACCCAGCACACCAGACACACCCUCUGAGUCACCUAGGCCGCCUGGGGCUGAGAAGACCUAACCGAGGGGCCAGAUGGCUUCGACCGGCUUAGAACUGCUGGGCAUGACCCUGGCUGUGCUGGGCUGGCUGGGGACCCUGGUGUCCUGCGCCCUGCCCCUGUGGAAGGUGACCGCCUUCAUCGGCAACAGCAUCGUGGUGGCCCAGGUGGUGUGGGAGGGCCUGUGGAUGUCCUGCGUGGUGCAGAGCACGGGCCAGAUGCAGUGCAAGGUGUACGACUCACUGCUGGCUCUGCCGCAGGACCUGCAGGCCGCACGUGCCCUCUGUGUCAUUGCCCUCCUGCUGGCCCUGCUUGGCCUCCUGGUGGCCAUCACAGGUGCCCAGUGUACCACGUGUGUGGAGGACGAAGGUGCCAAGGCCCGUAUCGUGCUCACCGCGGGGGUCAUCCUCCUCCUCGCCGGCAUCCUGGUGCUCAUCCCUGUGUGCUGGACGGCGCACGCCAUCAUCCAGGACUUCUACAACCCCCUGGUGGCUGAGGCCCUCAAGCGGGAGCUGGGGGCCUCCCUCUACCUGGGCUGGGCGGCGGCUGCACUGCUUAUGCUGGGCGGGGGGCUCCUCUGCUGCACGUGCCCCCCGCCCCAGGUCGAGCGGCCCCGCGGACCUCGGCUGGGCUACUCCAUCCCCUCCCGCUCGGGUGCAUCUGGACUGGACAAGAGGGACUACGUGUGAGGCGGAGGUUUCCCCUGGGAGCCCACUGCUCCCCACUGCCCCGCCCUUUCGACCUUGGCCUGAUGACCAGAUGCCCUGCUCCAUCACAACCUCCUUCCCCAGGAAAACCCACUUUCCAAAAGCCCAAGCUACACCUGGCUGCAGGGCUGGGUCAGCUGGCCUGGCUGAGCUCUUCUCAGUGGGGUCCCCUUUGAUGUUCUCCCCCAAGUUGGGCAGCCUAGAGGUGUUGGGAACCCUGGCCUGCCCCCACCUCCCCAGUAAUUGUUUCCUUCCGUUGCCCAGGACACUGGCUGGCCUUCCUUCUCUUCUGAGCCCUCCCCUGCCCCAGGAACCCUGGCCUCACCAAAACAGCAGCAGCUCGUUGGCUCCAAAACCAGGGAGCAGACCAUGCCCUCCCAACCCUGGAGUUGUCAGGGAGGGCCUGCCCAUCACCUCCCUCUCCCCAACAUCCCCACCCUCGAGUUGGAAAUAAAGAGCAUUUGUAACUGG